ACAGAGGGUAACUCAGAUCAGGCUUAGAAAUCACUUGACUUAACUCAGCAGCACUUUUUCUUUUCUUUGUGUCUGUAUUAUUUUAGCAGCCUUCUCUAAAUACUGGAGGCAUUGGAUUUCAUGUCGCCAAAAGGAAUUUAAAAAUGACAAAAGUGUAAUCUGUUAGAAAUAGUUAAUUUGUAGAAUUUUACUCUAUAAGGAGGUUUAGUUUCAAUUUGUUUUGAAAUGAAGGAAUUAAGUUGUGUUUUUAACCAAAUGAAUUGGCAUCUUUAUAUUUAGGAGAAGUAACAUUGGUGAUUAUUUAUUUCAAGAAUCAUGACUGGAAAAAGCUUGGAAGUUUAGUAGAGGAGUAUAUGUUGUACAUGCAAAGACAAGAUCUGCAUGAAUCUAUGUAUUUCUGGGUGUCUGGUGAAGGCCACUUUAGGUGACUGGCCAGAGAAGGAGGUGCCCUAGUGAUCCUUGAGUCACAGCCAUACUGCUAGGACCAUGACUACCAUACCAAGAAAAGGCAGCAGCCACCUGCCUGGCAGUUUGCACACCUGUAAACUGAAGCUGCAGGAGGACCGGCGACAGCAAGAAAAAUCUGUCAUUGCUCAACCCAUAUUUGUUUUUGAAAAGGGAGAACAAACUUUUAAGAGACCUGCAGAAGACACCCUGUAUGAAGCAGCAGAACCAGAAUGUAAUGGUUUUCCAACAAAGCGUGUACGGUCUUCAUCUUUUACUUUUCAUAUUACAGAUUCUCAGUCCCAGGGAGUGUCAACCUUGUCUCAGAAGCAAAUGAGAUGUUCAUCCGUCACUAACCUCCCAACCUUCCCCCAUUCUGGGCCAGUGAGGAAAAACAAUGUUUUUAUGACAUCAGCUCUUGUGCAAAGUAGUGUUGAUAUAAAGAGUGCUGAACAAGGUCCUGUGAAACAUUCUAAACAUGUUAUUAGACCUGCUAUUUUGCAGCUACCUCAAGCUCGAAGUUGUGCAAAAGUAAGAAAAACAUUUGGACACAAGGCACUGGAAUCUUGCAAGACUAAAGAAAAAACAAAUAAUAAGAUUUCUGAGGGAAAUUCCUAUUUGUUAAGUGAAAAUUUAUCAAGGGCUAGAAUUUCAGUCCAGCUGUCUACUAACCAGGACUUUUUAGGUGCAACAUCAGUAGGAUGUCAACCAAAUGAAGAUAAAUGUUCUUUUAAAAGCUGCAGUUCCAAUUUUGUUUUUGGAGAAAACAUGGUAGAAAGAGUUUUGGGUACUCAAAAACUCACCCAGCCUCAACUUGAAAAUGAUUCAUAUGCCAAGGAAAAACCAUUCAAAUCCAUUCCGAAAUUUCCUGUCAACUUUUUAAGUUCAAGAACAGACUCUAUUAAAAAUACUUCCCUAAUUGAAUCAGCUGCUGCAUUCUCUUCCCAACCAUCACGAAAAUGCUUGCUGGAGAAAAUUGAUGUUAUAACAGGGGAGGAAACAGAACAUAAUGUGUUAAAGAUAAACUGCAAGCUUUUCAUAUUCAACAAAACAACACAAUCCUGGAUUGAAAGGGGCAGAGGAACGUUGAGACUGAAUGACACAGCAAGCACUGACUGUGGAACAUUACAGUCAAGACUAAUUAUGCGCAAUCAAGGCAGUCUAAGGCUGAUCCUCAACAGCAAACUCUGGGCCCAAAUGAAGAUUCAAAGAGCAAACCACAAAAAUGUACGAAUAACAGCUACUGAUUUAGAAGACUAUAGCAUCAAAAUAUUUUUAAUUCAGGCCAGUGCCCAAGAUACAGCAUAUUUGUAUGCAGCAAUACAUCAUCGUCUUGUUGCACUUCAAAGCUUCAAUAAGCAGAGAGAUGUCAAUCAAGCUGAAAGCCUGUCAGAAACAGCCCAACAAUUGAACUGCGAAAGCUGUGAUGAGAAUGAGGAUGAUUUCAUCCAAGUCACUAAAAAUGGAUCAGAUCCUUCUAGUUGGACUCACAGACAGUCGGUUGCCUGUUCAUGAAUACUACCUACUAUAAACAUGACAUCUACAAAAAGAGGGGUCACCCUACUGAAAAUACUAAACCACCCUAACUAAUGAGAAGAUUCUAUUCAUUCCUUGAAGAGUUUUUAUAGAAAAGUUUAAGAAAUGUAAUUUGUUGCAAUUAACAUUUUUAUGUUUUACAUUUUACAUUUUGAUUAUUGUGCAGAAACUGACAGAAUUUAAAAAAAUGGACUUCAGAAGUUCAAAAUUUAUCAUUUUUGAAGAAGUUUAUUUAGAAUAGGAUUUUAUAACUAAUUUGGACUCUUCAUCACAUUGAUGGAUAUAAUACUUAGAAUUAUAAAUUGCUAGAUUUGAUAAAUACCUAACAAAAUGUUUAUUUUUUUCAGUCAUACUUGACCACAAAACAAAUAUUUUACUAAAUUUCCAGAGUCAUUUCUCUGAAAAAUAGUAUAAUGGCAUGAUAACAUUUCACUAAAUCCUAUUUAUCUUCUGGGAAAUAUUUUAAUUUAGCUUUUGGAUUUCCUAAUAUGAUAAGCUUAUAUAUUCAUGGUAUGAAUUCCUUUAAAAAGAGCAUCUGCUCUUGGACUUGUAUCUGUUGCAUCUUGUCAAUGUUUGACUCAUGGUCAGCAUCCAAUAGUUGUUAAAUGAAUAAAUAAAAUAUAAUACAUUACCUAUGUAUCAAAAAGCAUGUGUAAGAAAGCCAAAUAUGUUAACUGUUCUACUUUAUUUAUGUAAUUAUAUUUUCAUUAGUAUUUUAGUAGAUGGGGCUGUAUAGAAAAACAAAUGUAUCAUAUGUAGCCAAAUGAAUCUUUUUCUUAAAUGAUAUUAUUAUAGUAGGCUACAGUAAUUUCAACAAUUUUACAAUAGAGUUUUGAUCCUCUUCUUUGCGAUUUGUUUCAGAGACACCUCAUGAAUCACACAAGAAAAUUAGUCUCAGUACUUAUAGCCCUAUUUCAUUUUUCAAUUCAGUUUUAUCACACCAUGGCUUCGAAGUGACUUUGAUUGUGACCCCUAAGCAAUUAUCUGAUUAGGGGAUAAAAAUUCAUAAUUCCAAGAUGUUUCUGAAAAUGUUCUGAACAAUGACAACAUAUUUGGAAUGAGGGCGUAAUUUCACUAAGUGAUGCUUCGAAGAACAAUAUUCAUUUGGAUAUGCAAACACACAUUUUCAAAAGUUAUAUUACUGUGUUACCAUACCUGUUAUAAAAUAAUAAAAAUAUAUAAGUAUUUAUUAAGUCAAACUUCAGCUACUGCCUGAAAGUUUAGCAUAUGAAAUUUAAAUUAAGUCUUUCAGAUUAUGAUUAUGACAAUUGUUCAACAUUUUGUCCUUCCUUAUAACUGAGAAAGCAUAACUUAAUAUAACUACUAAGAGAGGCCCAUUCAUUCUUCCAGUGAUUCUAGAAGAAAUAUGGCACAUAAUAUCCUUUACUUCUAAAUAAAGGAGUCAAUGACUCAGAAAAUAAAGAGGAAAAAUAAAGUAAAUGUGAGAGAGAUGAAGAAAAGAUAGAAGGGGAAAAAGAGAUUUAGUACGAAAGAAAGGACAAAAAGAAUGGACAACAGAAAUACUCUUUUUUAAAAUCAAGAAGAGUGACUCUGAUGCGGAACACACUCAGCAGAAAAUUUUCAUUAGAAACAUAACACAGAGAGAUAUUUGGAGAAGAUAAUAAAGCACUGGUUCUCUUUUAUUGUUAAGAUCUCAGCUGAUGUGGGAACAUUGUGAUUGCACUAUAAAUUGCUAAAGUGAAGAAGAGAACAAAUAACUUCAUUUAUUUAUUUUGUUUGUUUUUUAGACAGAGUCUCGCUCUGUCACCCAGGUUGGAGUGCAGUGGCACGAUUUCGGCUCACUUCAACCUCCCCCUCCCGGGUUCAAGGGAUUCUCGUGCCUCACUCAGCCUCCUGAGUAGCUGGGAUUACAGGCGCCCGCCAUCAUACCUGGCUAAUUUUUGUAUUUUUAGUAGAGACGGGGUUUCACCAUGUUGGCCAGGCUGGUCUUGAACUCCUGAUCUCAAGUGAUACACUUUGCCUCAGCCUCCCAAAGUGUUGGGAUUACAGGCGUGAGCCACCACACCUGGUCAUCUUUAUCUUUUUGACAUGUUCAUCCUCGUCCCCACACUAAGGUAGAGAUAAAGCAAUUAUCUUCUCAAUGCUUGAAACAUUUUAAGUUGAAUUCAUUCUAUGAUUUUCUUUAGAUUUCUCCGCAUAUAUCAAUGGAAAAAAUUAACUAUCUUAAUUUCUCAUCUAUAUAGAAAUGCCAGUGCAACAAAACCAAAUGUAGGGUUAGAAUAUCAGCAAGGCAAAGAGAGAAGAGAAAAUUCCCAGAUUAUGAAAUGGAGAAGAAGAACAGAAACAUGAUAUUUAGCUCACAACUCUUUCAACCCAUUUUCUAUACACUCCAUUAUUCUUUCUUAGAAUUCUUACACAAAUAUUUAGUACAAUUUUGGAGGAAUAGUAGAAACAUUUUAUAGUUUUUCCUUGUCCUGUAUCUUCAUCUAGCCUUCUUUUCAGCUUUCCUAUGUCCUUUGUUCUCCUUUUAUAAGGAGAGAUGAGUUGUACAAUAACAUCCAUUUUCAUAAGUUAUUUAGGUAAAUUAUUUUGAAGUAUACAUGUUGGAUUUCCAAAGCAGCUGUUUUUAAUUAAAAUUUAAUUAACUAAUUUAUGUCAUUAUAUAUCUUGUGUUAAGACAACCUUAACUUUCUUUUAGUAAGAUUUUACCCAACUGUUUACCCUAAUUAUAGACAAUUAAAAUGUUCUCUCUUAAAAAA